AGCAGCAGUGGCAGCGGCGACCGGAGCCCGCAGCAGCUCCGAGCGCCUCCGGGAGGACAGGCGGCGAGCUCGGCGAAUCGUCAUCUGCCAGCCGAUCGCGGCGCUCCGCGGGCCGGGGCCGGGAGCCCGGGGCGAGCCCGAACGCGGCUUCUUCUCCGCCCGCCGCGGAGACUCUGCCGGGUGGGCUGCGGGCGCCCCUCGCUGCCGCCUGUGAACGCUGUGGGUGCGCGGGGCUGCGGCCACGGCGGCGGUGGCGGCGGCGGCGGGAGCCGCGAGUCGGGGCCGCCCGGGCUGUGCUUCGCCCCGGCAGCAGCGGUGGCGGCGGCGCCUGUGGCUCAGGAUGCGGCCGGGGGGCGCACUGCUCGCCCUGCUCGCCAGCCUGCUGCUGCUGCUGCUGCUGCGCCUGCUCUGGUGCCCGGCAGACGCGCCCGGCCGCGCCAGGAUUCUGGUGGAGGAAAGCAGGGAGGCCACCCACGGCACCCCCGCAGCGCUGAGGACGCUCCGGAGCCCGGCGACCGCGGUACCGCGCGCCACUAACAGCACAUAUCUGAAUGAGAAGUCGCUCCAACUGACGGAGAAAUGCAAAAAUCUGCAAUAUGGCAUUGAGUCUUUCUCUAACAAAACGAAAGGGUGUGACCCGACACUCCUGGCCUACAUCCUUGACUGAAAGAAGUGCUGCAUCACGGAACAAACGCUAAGGUAUUCAGAGAACGACUACCUUCAGAUUAUCACAGAUAUACAGAGUUGUCCAUGGAAACGGCAAGCAGAAGAAUAUGCAAAUUUUAGAGCCAAACUUGCUUCCUGCUGUGAUGCUGUUCAAAACUUUGUUGUUUCUCAGAAUAACACUCCAGUUGGGACUAAUAUGAGUUACGAGGUGGAAAGCAAAAAAGAAAUCCCAAUUAAGAAGAACAUUUUUCAUAUGUUUCCAGUGUCCCAGCCUUUUGUGGACUACCCUUAUAAUCAGUGUGCAGUGGUCGGAAAUGGGGGAAUUCUGAAUAAGUCUCUCUGUGGAACUGAAAUAGAUAAAUCCGACUUCGUUUUUAGGUGUAACCUACCCCCAACCACAGGAGAUGUUAGUAAAGAUGUUGGCAGUAAAACAAAUCUUGUGACUAUAAAUCCAAGCAUCAUAACUCUGAAAUAUGGGAACUUAAAGGAAAAAAAAGCCCUAUUUCUGGAGGACAUUGCAACCUAUGGAGAUGCAUUUUUUCUUCUGCCAGCAUUUUCCUUCAGGGCCAACACGGGUACCUCUUUCAAAGUAUACUACACGCUCGAAGAGUCUAAAGCAAGACAAAAGGUUCUAUUUUUCCAUCCCAAGUACCUGAAAGAUCUGGCCCUUUUCUGGAGAACUAAAGGUGUGACUGCAUACCGCUUGUCCACCGGCUUGAUGAUCACAAGUGUUGCAGUGGAACUGUGUAAAAAUGUGAAGCUGUAUGGAUUCUGGCCCUUCUCUAAAACUGUAGAAGACAUACCUGUCAGCCAUCACUAUUAUGACAACAAGCUACCUAAACAUGGUUUCCAUCAGAUGCCCAAAGAAUACAGCCAGAUCCUCCAACUUCACAUGAAAGGAAUCCUCAAACUGCAAUUUAGCAAAUGUGAAGUCGCCUAAACAAAGUAUCUUAAAAUGGGAAUAAUUUUAAUAUAAUGCAGUAGGUGAUUAACAAUGUCUCCAAACACCAAAGGAGGUGGCUAAAGAGUAUUUUGAGAUGAGCCCCAAAAUUUGGUUUGACCAAAGCUUCCCCACUCAUUUUGCAAUGAUGGCAAGUCAUUCAAUCCUUCUCAUCUUCAUUUUUUCUCCUUAUAACAUGGACACCAUAUCUGACUCAUACAAAUUUUUAUAAUUUAUGAAAAUUAUUGGCAUGGCCUUUGGUGUGAGGUAGGGACUCAAAGAAUAUUUCUUUCUUACUAUUUAUACCAGCCAUCUCCACCUUCACCAGACCGAUAAUAAAAGCAUGCUUUCUUGGAGAUCUCUUCUAAAGAGAAUAGCUGCAUUACCAGUAUCCAUUGGAUUUCUUUCUGUGGCAGGUCUCUAUCAAUAAUAUCCUUCCCAUUUUUCUGUCUCAAAGACUGCAUGCAAGAAAAUUAUAUACUUAAGCAAAAAGUUCUUGAUCAUUCGGGAAUGAAAUUCUUCUCUGAGUAUGGCAGUAUGCCUGCUUCUGAUUAAAUUCACUUUUAAUAGUAGCUGUGAUGAUAUUUUGGUUGAAUUUAAGCCAUUUAUUUUCCUCUUAUGUCUACAUUUCUUCAUCACUUAAUAAUUUUAUUUUAACUUCCUGCCUCAUUCUUACACUUUUUUCUCUCUCACUUAUACGAUAUACUUCAAGGACGUGAACAGUUACAAUACCCAGUCUUUCUUACCUGUUGUCUUGCCUGUGGGGUCACUCACUCAAUUUUAUUUUAAAAUUACUGAAUAACUACUUCAUGCCAGGCCCUGCACCAGGCUCUGUGAGAGGACAAGAAGGAUUAUUGCCUCUUGUAGGAGAAAACAGAUGUGCAUAUCAUUAAUUAUGAUGGGGUAUGAUAAGUAUUACAAUGACAAAAGCUAUGAAUAAAGUGCUACAAGGAACAGAAGCAGGGAUAAUUAAAUCCAUUUCAGUGGAAUCUAUUUCAAUGUACAAUAGUCUCCCCUAAUCUGCAGAUAUGGGAAGACCCCCUGUGGAUGCCUGAAACCAUUGAUGAUAUUAGAAAUAUGUAAUUGAUUAGUAAAAGUAACAAAAUAUACUGAAAUAAUUAAAUAUACAAUGUGGGGACUUUAUAUGCUAUUUUAAUAAAACUUACAUAUAGUUAGGACAUUUAGAGCUUACUUUUUUUUCCCAUAUAAUAUCCUAUCUUAAAAAUUUUUCUUUAGAACAUCAAAACAGAAUCUCUAGUAUCACUGAUAUGGAUUUCAGAAAUAUUCCAAAUGGUGUGAGAUCAAACAGCAUAGUGAUACCCAUGUUCCAGUAAAAGCUUAGGAGAAAAAGAAUGUUUGCGGGUUUUCUUUUGUGGAGAAAAUUGUAGACAUUUCCAAGUUAACACAUCUGAAGUUUCUGGUUCGACAUCUGUGUUGCCAUCCUAAAAGCACGUGUGAAAUUUUACAACAAUCCUACCUAGAUUCACGUUAGCCAAAAAUCUUUGGCUAAACAGACACCCCGAGAUUUCAUAAAGUGUGUUAUAGUCAGAAUUGGUGGUAAUUAAUCUACAAAUCUGCAAAAUAGUGUUCAUAGUUUUUCUUUUUAUUUUGAUCUUGGUGAAAAACUUGCAGUAACUCACCAUUACAGAGCGACAAGAACUGUGACGCAUGUUUUAUGAUUUACAUAGCUGAUGUGGUGUAUUAUCGAUAUCCAUAAUCUGUCAUAUUUAGACACAUUCAUUGUGACACAUAUAACAUGUGCAUUCUUUUUAUCUUUUUCUCAAGUGGGUCUAUAGUUGUGAUUUCACAGCAGAUUGGGGUUGUUGGCCAUUGUUUGAAGCUCUCCUACUCUCUUUCUAGCAUAGUCAGUGUGUUGCAGAGAACUAAAGGGAGUAAAAGACACAGUGCCUCAUUGAAUCCUAACAUUUUCUUCCUGGUAGGGCAUAUAUCCCACCUUCCAUAUAUCCUGCUGUGAGGUGCCAAUAAUGUUCUUUUGUUCCAAAACAGAACAUUACUUAGAACUUUCUAAAAUAUGAUAGAACAUGAAUGUUUACAAUACAGCAUGUCAGCUAUGUAAACUGUAAAACGUAAGUCACAGUUCUUUUUGUUCUGUAUUGGUGAAUCAUUGCAAAUUUUUCACCAAGUGCAAAACAAAAAGAAAAACUAUAAACUCCAUCUUGUAGAUUUGUAGAUUCGCCACAACCAAGUCUGACUGUGACACUCCCAAGAAAUCUGUAUGUAAUCAGCAUUGCUUAAAUAUUGUUAGAUCUAAUGUGAUCUUCUGCUCUUAAAACUCAAGUACAUCUAAGGGCAUUGAGAAUGGAAAGUCUGAGUUCUGGUACUAGACAAGAGCAGCCCUUUAGGCCAGGCGCAAUGGCUCACACCUGUAAUCCCAGCACUUUGGGAGGCCAAGGUGGGUGGGUCACUUGAGGCCAGGAGUUUGAGACUAGCCUGGGCAACAUAGUGAGUACCCUUCUCUACAAAAAACAAAAAAAUUAGCUGAGCAUAGUGGCGUGCACCUGUGGUCCCAGCUACUUGGGAGGCUAAGGAGGGAGGUUCACUGGAGCCCAGGAGGUAGAGGCUGCAGUGAGCUGUGAUCUUACCACUGCAUUCUAGCCUGUGUGACAGAGUGAGACCCUGUCUCAAAAAAGAAAAAAAAAAAGUAGCCCUUUAGUUAGGAUUCUAGCUCAUAACGCUGCAUACUACCAGUUUCUAAGAGAAAUACUAGCUUGCUGGAUUCUAUUUUCCACUUGUUGUUCAGCCUCAUUGAGCAAUGAAACAGAAUAACAAGAUUCCAAUAUAAUUUUCAGCCAAAUCCAAAGGCAAGGCAGAAAUAUUCAUUUAAGUAUAUAGUCCAUAGUACUCUGUGGUCCCUGCAAAGGGCUUCAUGAUCAAUUGCAUAGUGUUAAUUUUUGCGCAGUGUAAUAAUCCUCGAACAUCCUUGAAGUCUCUGGUGCUUUUCCCUUGGAACAAAAGGCAAUGACAAAUAGAUCAUGGCUUUCACUAAAGGAUAUUUCCUUCUUCAUGUAAGUCCUAACCCAGUAACUGCGUGGGCUCUCAGCCAGGUAAUCAGUCAAAAAGUCUUUUUUUGAGGACUCUCUGUAGAAUACAGAAUUAAGCAGCAAAUCAGACCUGUGUUUGCCUAAAUUUUUCCUUGCUUAUAAAAAAUUUACCAGCUAAGUAUUAUGUAAUGUCAAGUACCGUAAAUCACUCCAUGAAUUAGGAAGCUUUGGGAAAAGUGGAAAAUUUUGUGGAAAACAGGUCCACUAACAUCCUAAACAGCUACUGCAGAAGUAUAGUUAAGAUGUGAUAUAUAAUAUAUUGUGAUCUUCAAGACAUUUUAUUUAUCUAACAUGACAUGGAAACACAUUAUUAUGCCAUUAAAAAUUGAAGGCAUUGUAGGAAUUCAUCUGAUAUAUCUGAUGCACUUGAUCUGAUAAAUCCACUUGAGGCUGCUAGGAGUGUUGAAGAUUUCCUAUUUACAUGUGGCUUCAGAAGGCUGAUCCCAUAGCGAGGAACAGUGUCACCAGUACCCUCCUGAGAGUGGAAAGGCAAGAAUAUUUCUCAUGGUCUUUCUUAUUUUGGGUCAUCACUCUUCCAGAAGCAUUCUUCUUUUUAUAAAAAAAAUGUGGGUGAUAUAUGAUAAAGAUGCGCUACUUAUGUAAUGGAGACAGGGCAAACUCUUUAGCAGAUAAUAUUGAAACAUUGGCUCACUCUAUGGAGAAAAAUAAAUGCCUACAUUGCACCAUAUAAAAAGUUGGGCUCCAGAGGGAUGAAAACGAUGGAUUAAAAAGAAAACUUUAAAGCUCAUAGAAGAAAAUGUAGGAGAAUUAUGUUUGAGAUACAGGUGAGGAACUGUACUUCUUCAACAUGACCCAAAAAUAUCUUUUUAAAUAGUUGGGUUAAGAAAGGAUGGCUAUGACUGUAUUAAAAUGAAAGAGUUCUAGUCAGUGAAUGACACCUUAAAGUUAAUAGGCUGGGGACAGACUGAAAUAGCUUUUAGUAAUGCAUAAAAUUAAUGACAUUAAUAGAGAGACAUUCCAAGGAAUUGUAAAUCAACAAGUAAAAGACAGGAAACUCAAUAUAAAAAUGAACAAAAGAUAAGAAUGUGAUUUACAAAGGGGAAAGCUGAGUAGCUAAUAAGAAUAGGAAGUGAUACUCAAAUUUACCAGUAACCUGAGAAAUGCAAAUGAAAGUGAGAUACUACAUCCAUUGCAUUGGUAAAAAUGAGUAAGGUCAUUAACUUCAAGUGUGGAAGUAUAAGCUGAUUGAAUCAUUUUGGAAAGCAACCUAGGAGUACUGAGUUAGUAAAAUUCAUCAUAUGUCUGUCCUAUAGUCCAGUAAUUGCACUUUUGCAUAUACAGCCAAGAGGACCUGUUCUGAUCCACACAAAAAAACAAGUAUUAAGGUAUUUAUUCCAUUAUGGUUUGCGGUAGUAAGUAGACAAAUUGGACUCACAGAUAUCUGUCUCUUCGGAAGUCAGUGAACUAACUUGACUGGAUCCAUAGUGUGGAAUAUGAUACAGCAGUUAGAAGCAACUUACUGGACAUAUAUACAGAAAUAAGGGUAUGUCCUUUAAAUUUAGCAUAAAGGGAAAACAAAAGCUUUAGCACAAUGCCAUUUAAUUACUUUAAAGCGUAUGCAUGCAUACAUACAAACAUAUUCAAGGCUACGUGUCAAAUACAAGAAGGGUACCCAUUAAGAAGAGGGUAAUCGGAGUGGGUUUAGGGAUAAAGAAGAAAAAUAUACAUGUUAUUAUAUUUAAUACAGCAAGCCUUUGACAUAUAUAUUCUUAUACUCACAUAUGAUAUUCUUACUACUACAUAAAUAAAUAUAGAAGCUGACUCAAAAUUGUAAGUAACUUAUAUAAGGUUGCAUUAUAUAUAAGAGCAGAGCUAGUAUUCAACUCAUAUGUCUGACUCUAAAGCCAAUAUUAUUUCCAUUAUGCAAUUAUAAAAUGAAAAGAAAAAUCAGUAUUAUCCCAUGUCAUUGACAUGUAAUAAAUGGCACAUAUUUAUGUACAUGCAUAUACCCAUGAAACCGUCUCUCCAAUUAAGACAAUGUAUAUAUUCAUUACCCCAAAAUGUUUUCUUGUGCUACUUUGUAAUCCCUCCCUCUUCUUCCUCCCUGUCCAUCCCACCCUCGUCCCCAGAAAAUUCCUAAUCUGUUUUUCUAUAGACAUUUACAUUUUUACACUAUAGACUGUUUACAUUUUUUAGAAUUUUAUAUAAAUGGAAUCUUACUGUCUGUACUCAUUUCUUGUCUUGCACUUUUGCUCGACAUAAUAAUAUUAAAACUCAUUCAUGUUGAUUGUGUAUCUGUAGUUUAUGCCUUUAUUUACUGAGUAGAAUUAUGUUAUAUGGAUGGACCACAGUUGGCUUAUCUGCUCAUUUGUUGAUGAACAUUUUACUAUCUCCUGGUUUUGGCUAUUACAAAUAAAGGUAUCAUGAACAUUAA